GUAGAGUUAGAAAAACAUGAACCAUUAACAGAUGUGGCCUCCCUGCAGAACUUUUACUUUGAAAAAGAAGUACGUCUGAACCAGAUUCACAUGUUUGAUAUUUGGAUGCAGAGAAAAUGGGGCAGAAAGCAUCGCAACAGUUGGCUCUGAAGGACAGCAAAGAGGUGCCCGUCGUCUGUGAGGUGGUCAGUGAAGCUAUAGUCCAUGCAGCUCAGAAACUGAAGGAGUACCUUGGAUUUGAAUAUCCUCCAAGUAAACUCUGCCCAGCUGCAAAUACUCUGAAUGAGAUCUUCUUAAUCCAUUUCAUCACUUUCUGCCAAGAAAAGGGAGUUGAUGAGUGGCUGACCACCACCAAGAUGACCAAGCACCAAGCCUUCCUGUUUGGUGCAGACUGGAUUUGGACCUUUUGGGGAUCCAACAAGCAAAUAAAGCUUCAGCUCGCAGUACAGACUCUGCAGAUGUCUUCACCUCCUCCUGUGGAAUCUAAGCCUUGUGACCUUUCCAAUCCAGAAUCAAGGGUAGAGGAGUCUUCCUGGAAGAAAAGUAGAUUUGAUAAGCUGGAAGAAUUCUGUAACUUAAUAGGAGAGGAUUGCCUGGGUCUGUUUAUCAUCUUUGGUAUGCCAGGAAAGCCUAAAGACAUCAGGGGAGUUGUCCUGGACAGUGUCAAAAGUCAGAUGGUGAGGAGCCAUCUGCCAGGAGGGAAGGCUGUGGCUCAGUUUGUCCUGGAAACUGAAGAUUGUGUGUUCAUCAAAGAGCUGCUCAGAAAUUGUCUGAGUAAGAAAGACGGGCUGAGAGAGGUGGGCAAGGUUUAUAUCAGCAUUCUCUGACUUGGAUAUGUAUUAUGUGAGUGGCCUGUAAGAGGAAAAGAAAAAAAGAUUCUAAUAAGCAAGCUCACCUAUUUGCAUCAUUCCAGCAUGGGAUUUUUUUUCAUUUGUUUUCCCAUUGAUUGAAAAUGAUUACUGGGAUCAAAGUACAUUCAUGUCGCAAUUACAGAGAGAGAGAGAAAAAAAGAAAACCCUGGCUCUGCCUAUGAUUUAAAAACAGUUCAGGAAAAGUUAUAAUUUAGUUUAAUAUUUCAUUCACUUAUUCAAUAAUAAAAAUGGAAGAGAGAUAAUAAAGUCACAUUUAAAGUUUGAUUUGCAAAAAAAAA